CUCUCCCGCGAGCGCGGGCGUCGGAAGCGGCGGAGGUGGCAGUGUCUGCCCUGGGAUGGCCUUCCCUGCACGCGCGCGUUUGUAUCUAAAUCGCAGGGGACCGUCUCUUCCUCAGCUUGCCGGCGCGAGGAGCCAGAGCCUCGAGUUAGGGCCACACGGGGGAAUUUGGGGCGGGUUGACUUUUCCCGCAACAUAUUUUGUCAGAGACCUUGGAGAAAGUCCUACUGCUGGCGCCUUUUAGUUUCCUCAGAUGAUAACAUUCCCAACUCCGCUCGAAGCGUCCAGUCUUAAUCCCCUCCAGCAGAAUGGUGCUGACUAACUCAGAUGUCUGAGAUCCGCAGCUGUGUCAAUAAUAGGGCUUUCUGGCAAACUUGUGAACGUAGGCUCGAAAUUGUUUUUCUGGACGCUUGAAUAUCAGUAUAUUCAGUUGAAAACAUGUGAUUUUGUUGCCAGUUUAUCAGUUCCUACCUGGCCUCCCGAGGUCAGUCCUUCAGGACUGACGCUGCAACUCCAACUCCCAUGUUUCUUUUAAAUCACAAAGGAAAAUAUCUUUUAAAAAUCAGGAUACACUGAUUAAUUAUGUUAGUAACUAAUUGGCAUUUGUUGAAUCAAAAAGUUUUGGAAGCGUUAAAUAGUUUUAGCCUCUAAUUUUACAAUAAAGUGAAGCUCAAAGUUGGGAAUUUGACCGGAUGAGGGCUACAAGCCUAUCCUUUCCUCCUCCCUCUUCAUCUUUCCCAACCUGUCACCCUGGCUCGUUUAUGUCUCUGUAUAGUUGUAGGCUUUCAUCAUUAUACAGAGAAAAUAACAAAGUAAGUAGUGUCUUCUAAACAUCUAGCCAUUAAUUCCACCAAUCCAUUCCAUUUUCAUUCAAGAAAUACCAGAGAUGCUGAGUAAAGAUUAAUUAGCUGCCUGGUUCCACAGAUACAUGGGAACAAAUCCAGAAUAGUAGUAGCUCAAAUCCAAAUAUAGUAACAAAUAGAAGUUAUAUAUUUUAAACGAAAAUAGUAGAUUUUCCCAUGAUCUCUUGAAAGAAAAAUAAAAUUAUAUUUUUAAAGUUUUGUUGAGUAGACUUGCAUUGUAGUUUUACGGAAUUAUUUUUAGUGUUACAAUCUUUAAAAGUUUUCCCCUUAGAUUGUUUAUCAGCCAGUCUCUCUCUCCCGAAGAGUUCUUUAGUUUUUGAGGAAGUUGAUUUGGAGGCAGUUCUUACAAUGAGUUAAGGGUUCCCAGUUGUGUUACAGUUUCUUUUUCCUUGAUAUCUCAUUUCUACUCUGCCAACAAGAACACCAUGCACCCCAGCUCUAAAGAAGGAAGACUUUCAAGAAUGGAGUGUAGUGGCAUGAUCACAGUUCAUUGCAGCCUCAACCUCCUACGCUCAAGUGAUCCUCCCACCUGAGCCUCCUGAGUAGCUGGGAUCACAGGCGCAUGCUACCACGCCCGGCUGAAGGUUUUUCAAUUUUUGAAGAGACGAGGUCCCACUGUGUUGCCCAGCCCCCUUGUCAGCGGAGCUAUAAGGUGAACUGCAGGAAGAUCCCAGCCCUAUACACGUGGGGCAGAGCCAGCAGAGGCCAGAGCUGUUGCUCUGUGCAGACCACGAGAGGAUGUCUCCCAGCCUUCAGGAAGGCGCUCAGCUCGGGGAAAACAAACCCUCAACUUGCUCCUUUUCAAUUGAGAGAAUCUUAGGACUGGACCAGAAGAAAGACUGUGUUCCAUUAAUGAAACCCCACAGGCCCUGGGCAGACACCUGCAGCUCAUCAGGGAAAGAUGGUAACUUAUGUCUACAUGUCCCAAAUCCUCCCAGUGGGAUUUCAUUCCCUAGCGUGGUGGAUCACCCAAUGCCAGAAGAAAGAGCUUCGAAAUAUGAAAAUUACUUUUCAGCCUCAGAAAGACUGUCUUUGAAAAGAGAGUUGAGUUGGUAUAGAGGCCGAAGACCAAGAACUGCUUUUACUCAAAACCAGAUUGAAGUGUUAGAAAAUGUCUUUAGAGUAAACUGCUAUCCUGGUAUCGAUAUUAGAGAAGACUUAGCUCAAAAAUUGAAUCUAGAGGAAGACAGAAUCCAGAUUUGGUUUCAAAAUCGGCGUGCAAAACUGAAAAGGUCCCAUAGAGAAUCACAGUUUCUAAUGGCGAAAAAAAAUUUCAACACAAAUCUGCUGGAAUAGAUAGAAAACUAAACAAGUGAAAUUAUCUUCUAAUUGCAGAGCAUGAAGAAUCAGUGGAAAUAUUAAGUGUUAAAAUGUGAUGUUUUCUUUCCUGCAUUUAAUCUGAAUAUUGUCAUUUUUUCUGAAAAUAUAUUGUAAAUACUAUUAUAGCAUGGUACAUAUUUGGGCACUUUUAGUUAUAGUAAAGACCUUUUAUAUAUAUUUUAAUAAACAUUUUCAGAAAAGAUUGCUAUUUUUUAAGUAAGCCAAAUUAAUCUAAUAAAUUAGUUUGUUAAAAUCAAUAGACUCAUGACUAAGUGAUUCCACAAGCUGGAUUCUAAUUAUAAAGUAUUUCAAGUAAAAUAAUCUGAAGAACAAAA